AAAAGAGAAGGUGGAUGGAGAAGGGGAAACUGGGCCUCAGCCAGCACCGGGAUGAUGCGACCAGCUUUGUCAGCACGCUUGGGGAGCAUACACACCGCUUGCCUUGGCUGGACCGGAGACUGUGAUCACCACCCUUCCAACCCAUCCCCCAACACGCAGGCUGGCAUGGCCACGCCCACAGUGCCCCAAGUGCUGCCUGCCUUGCAGUGACUCACUUCCUCUGUAUGGGCUGCUGAACUGUCCCAAGGAGAGGACAGGCCAUCUCCAGGCCUUCAGCCCCGAGUUUAGAUAUCUGGGCAGGCUUUGUGGAUGGGCAAGCAUACAGGGAGCCCAAAUGUGGAAGGUAGGUUUUUUCAGGUCAGGUGGAACUGUUAACACUGAAGCCUAUUUGGGUAAGAAGCAGAGCCUAGCUAGUACCUAAUGGAGAUUCAGGGGCCAGGAGUAUCGGGGAGGAAACAUUUCCUAACAGAGAGGUAAAAUAGCCAAGAGGAGUUUCUAUGUAUUCUGAAAUCAGGCAAUGGAAAGUAUUUGCAGAAAAGCAAUGUAGGGACCAGGCGUGGUGGCUUAUGCCUGUAAUCCCAACACUUUGGGAGGCCGAGGUGGGUGGAUCACCUGCGGUCAGGAGUUCAAGACCAGCCUGCCCAACAUGGUGAAACCUCAUCUCUACUAAAAAUACAAAAGUUAGCUAGGCAUGGUGGCACAUGCCUGUAGUUCCAGCUACUUUGGAGGCUGAGGCAGGAGAAUUGCUUGAACCUAGGAGGGUGAGGUUGCAGUGAGCCGAGAUCAUGCCACUGCCCUCCAGCCUGGCAACAGAGUGAGACUCCAUCUCAAAAAUAAAUAAAAGGCUGGGUGCAGUGAUUCAUGCCUAUAAUUCCAGCACUUUGGGAGGCCGAGGUGGGCGGAUAACCUGAGGUCAAGAGUUUGGGACCAGCCUGGCCAACAUGGUGAAACCCUGUCUCUACUAAAAAUACAAAAAUUAGCUGGGUGUGGUGGUGGGCCCUGUAAUCCCAGCUACUCGGGAGGCUGAGGAAGGAGAAUCACUUGAACCUGGGAGGCAGAGGUUACAGUGAGCUGAGAUCACACCACUGCACUCCAGCCUGGGUGACAGAGUAAGACUCGGUCUCAAUAAAUAAAUAAAUAAAAGCAAUGUGGGACUUGGAGGCUGAAGAGGUGGACAUGCAUGAACAGUGGAGGCGGUGUAUGUGGCUGCCUUUCCCCUGUAUUCCACUGAGAGGGAGCCCAAAUCUGCCUCGCCUGCAUUGAGGGAUGAAGAAAACACUGAGAGGCAGCUGAGAAACAUGGAUGCUAGUUCCAACUCCAUGGCCUCGGGAAGUCACUCAGACUCCUUGAGUCAGUAAUGAAAAGGUAGUAGAUUAGAGGCUGGGCGCAGUGGCUCAUGCCUGUAAUCCCAACACUUUGGGAGGCCGAGGUGGGCGGAUCACAAGGUCAGGAGUUCAAGACCAGCCUGGCCAACAUGGUGAAACACUGUCUCUACUAAAAAUACAAAAAUUAGCUGGGCAUGGUGGUGCAUGCCUGUAAUCCCAGCUACUCAGGAGGUUGAGGCAGGAGAAUUGCUUGAACCAGGGAGUCGGAGGUUGCAAUGAGCCGAGAUCGCGCCAUUGCACUCUAACCUGGGCAACAGAGUGAGACUCUGUCUCAAAAAAAAGAAAAGAAAAGGUGGUAGAUUAGAUCCUCUCUAAGAUUUCCUCCAACUCUGCAAUUCUAAAAUGUACAACAUGGGGAAGGAAGGUGAUCAGUACAACUGUAAACAACUGCAAUCCGGCCCUGAAGUUGAACAAAACAAAACCUAGGGAGAGGAAUGAGUUUGUAGCAGGUUUCAAUGCAGCGAUUGUGAACGCAUCACACACACACUCCUCACAGGCAAGGACUUCGCUUCUGCCAUGUGACUGAGACUCUGUUGGACUUCUCCAAAUUCAGAGUUCAGCCUGGCAUGCCGGCCAGGAGCCCCUUGGAGAGAUUCGGCGUGAGGAAACAGGAGGCCUCACGCUUCCUUCGGUUCUCCCUAAAUCUGCUGGGCAGGUAGCCAGAAGAAACUCUGAAGGGUACAGAAAGCCGAGGGCCAGGGGGACCCCGGCUGCGGAGCUGCAGUACCGUGUUUACCCAGCCUAACUGCGGUCACCCAGUCUCCUGCAUGUGUCUGAGGUCAGCCUCGGGGGCUCCCCUGAGUAGGUAUCUACCUGAGGCUCUUCCCCUGAUGCUACCUGCAUACCAAUUCCACCCAGGAACCUGGCGUCCUCAGGAGGCUGCACUUCCCAAGUGGGCUGAGACAGCCCCUUAAUAUGUGGGGCUGGAGCCAGAGACCUCAAGGGGCCACUAGGGGGCUCGAGACUCUCAGUGGCUGCUGACGCCCUCUUGUGGCCAUUUUGGGGAUUGGCCAGAAAAGUUUCAGAAGCGAGCCAAGAUCGGAAUUCUUAAGGAGGCCACACCGGAGGCAGUGCUCACACAGGCAAGCUACCAGGCCACAACAACGACACCCACCUCACCUCUGGCACCUCUGAGCAUCCACGUACUUGCAAGAACUCUUGCUCACAUCAGCUAAGAGAUUGCACCUGCUGACCUAGAGAUUCCGGCCUGUGCUCCUGUGCUGCUGAGCAGGGCAACCAGUAGCACCAUGUCUGUGACUGGCGGGAAGAUGGCACCGUCCCUCACCCAGGAGAUCCUCAGCCACCUGGGCCUGGCCAGCAAGACUGCAGCGUGGGGGACCCUGGGCACCCUCAGGACCUUCUUGAACUUCAGCGUGGACAAGGAUGCGCAGAGGCUACUGAGGGCCAUUACUGGCCAAGGCGUGGACCGCAGUGCCAUUGUGGACGUGCUGACCAACCGGAGCAGAGAGCAAAGGCAGCUCAUCUCACGAAACUUCCAGGAGCGCACCCAACAGGACCUGAUGAAGUCUCUACAGGCAGCACUUUCCGGCAACCUGGAGAGGAUUGUGAUGGCUCUGCUGCAGCCCACAGCCCAGUUUGACGCCCAGGAAUUGAGGACAGCUCUGAAGGCCUCAGAUUCUGCUGUGGACGUGGCCAUUGAAAUUCUUGCCACUCGAACCCCACCCCAGCUGCAGGAGUGCCUGGCAGUCUACAAACACAAUUUCCAGGUGGAGGCUGUGGAUGACAUCACAUCUGAGACCAGUGGCAUCUUGCAGGACCUGCUGUUGGCCCUGGCCAAGGGGGGCCGUGACAGCUACUCUGGAAUCAUUGACUAUAAUCUGGCAGAACAAGAUGUCCAGGCACUGCAGCGGGCAGAAGGACCUAGCAGAGAGGAAACAUGGGUCCCAGUCUUCACCCAGCGAAAUCCUGAACACCUCAUCCGAGUGUUUGAUCAGUACCAGCGGAGCACUGGGCAAGAGCUGGAGGAGGCUGUCCAGAACCGUUUCCAUGGAGAUGCUCAGGUGGCUCUGCUCGGCCUAGCUUCGGUGAUCAAGAACACACCGCUGUACUUUGCUGACAAACUUCAUCAAGCCCUCCAGGAAACUGAGCCCAAUUACCAAGUCCUGAUUCGCAUCCUUAUCUCUCGAUGUGAGACUGACCUUCUGAGUAUCAGAGCUGAGUUCAGGAAGAAAUUUGGGAAGUCCCUCUACUCUUCUCUCCAGGAUGCAGUGAAAGGGGAUUGCCAGUCAGCCCUCCUGGCCUUGUGCAGGGCUGAAGACAUGUGAGACUUCCCUGCCCCACCCCACAUGACAUCCGAGGAUCUGAGAUUUCCGUGUUUGGCUGAACCUGGGAGACCAGCUGGGCCUCCAAGUAGGAUAACCCCUCACUGAGCACCACAUUCUCUAGCUUCUUGUUGAGGCUGGAACUGUUUCUUUAAAAUCCCUUAAUUUUCCCAUCUCAAAAUUAUAUCUGUACCUGGGUCAUCCAGCUCCUUCUUGGGUGUGGGGAAAUGAGUUUUCUUUGAUAGUUUCUGCCUCACUCAUCCCUCCUGUACCCUGGCCAGAACAUCUCACUGAUACUCGAAUUCUUUUGGCAAA